UUCAAGACCAGCCUGGCCAACAUGGCGAAACAUUGUCUCUACUAAAAGUACAAAAAUUAGCCAGACGUGGUGGUGCUCACCUGUAAUCCCAGCUACUCGGGAGGCUGAGGCAGGAAAAUCACUUGAACCCGGGAGGCGGAGGUCACAGUUAGCCAAGAUCACACCACUGUACUCCAGCCUGGGUGAUAGAGUGAGACUCCAUCUCAAAUAAAUAAAUAAAUAAAUAAAUAAAUAAAUAAAUAAAUAAAUAAGUGAACCACGCAGGGUCCUUCCGGGGGGUGACCUUCAGCUGGCCAUUCGGGAUGAUGGACUUUCCAUCCCAGAACCAUGGCUCCAUUUGUCCGUAACCUUGUGGAGAAGACCCCAGCACUGGUGAAUGCUGCUGUGACUUACUUGAAGCCUCGAUUGGCCGCAUUUUGGUACUACACCACGGUUGAGCUGGUUCCUCCCACCCCUGCUGAGAUCCCUAGAGCUAUUCAGAGCCUGAAAAAAAUAGUCAGUAGUGCUCAGACUGGUAGCUUCAAACAGCUCACAGUUAAGGAAGCUUUGCUGAACGGUUUGGUGGCCACUGAGGUGUCGACGUGGUUUUAUGUCAGAGAGAUCACAGGCAAGCGUGGCAUCAUUGGCUAGAAUGUUUGAAGACCAGUCUUAACAUCUGAUUAUAUUUGAUUUAUUAUUUGAGUGUUGUUGGACCAGGUGUGAUCAGACUGCUAUCUGAAUAAAAUAAGAUUUGUCAGAAAUUCCAAAAAAAAAAAAAAGUGAAUCAAGCAGUUCCAACCCAUGUUCAAGGGUCAACUGU